GGUGCCGGCCGACAAACGACGCGGCGCGGGCGAGUGGGCGGAGGCGGCUGCGGGGAAGGCUGGGCUGCCGCGGGACGCGGUGAAGAUAGCCUGCGGAGUGUCCGGGCUGAACACGGUUGCAGCACUCCCAGUAGACCAGGAGCUCCGGGAGGCAGGGCCGGCCCCACGUCCUCUGCGCACCACCCUGAGUUGGAUCCUCUGUGCGCCACCCCUGAGUUGGAUCCAGGGCUAGCUGCUGUUGACCUCCCCACUCCCACGCUGCCCUCCUGCCUGCAGCCAUGACGCCCCUGCUCACCCUGAUCCUGGUGGUCCUCAUGGGCUUACCUCUGGCCCAGGCCUUGGACUGCCACGUGUGUGCCUACAACGGAGACAACUGCUUCAACCCCAUGCGCUGCCCGGCUAUGGUUGCCUACUGCAUGACCACGCGCACCUCUGCAGCCGAAGCCAUAUGGUGUCACCAGUGCACGGGCUUCGGAGGGUGCUCCCAUGGAUCCAGAUGCCUGAGGGACUCCACCCACUGUGUCACCACUGCCACCCGGGUCCUCAGCAACACCGAGGAUUUGCCUCUGGUCACCAAGAUGUGCCACAUAGGCUGCCCCGAUAUCCCCAGCCUGGGCCUGGGCCCCUACGUAUCCAUCGCUUGCUGCCAGACCAGCCUCUGCAACCAUGACUGACGGCUGCCCUCCUCCAGGCCCCCGGACGCUCAGCCCCCACAGCCCCCACAGCCUGGCGCCAGGGCUCACAGCUGCCCCUCCCUCGAGACUGGCCAGCCCACCUCUCCCGGCCUCUGCAGCCACCGUCCAGCACCGCUUGUCCUAGGGAAGUCCUGCGUGGAGUCUUGCCUCAAUCUGCUGCCGUCCAAGCCUGGGGCCCAUCGUGCCUGCCGCCCCUUCAGGUCCCGACCUCCCCACAAUAAAAUGUGAUUGGAUCGUGUGGUACAA